AGUCCCGACGUGGAACUCAGCAGCGGAGGCUGGACGCUUGCAUGGCGCUUGAGAGAUUCCAUCGUGCCUGGCUCACAUAAGCGCUUCCUGGAAGUGAAGUCGUGCUGUCCUGAACGCGGGCCAGGCAGCUGCGGCCUGGGGGUUUUGGAGUGAUCACGAAUGAGCAAGGCGUUUGGGCUCCUGAGGCAAAUCUGUCAGUCCAUCCUGGCUGAGUCCUCGCAGUCCCCGGCAGAUCUUGAAGAAAAGAAGGAAGAAGACAGCAACAUGAAGAGAGAGCAGCCCAGAGAGCGUCCCAGGGCCUGGGACUACCCUCAUGGCCUGGUUGGUUUACACAACAUUGGACAGACCUGCUGCCUUAACUCCUUGAUUCAGGUGUUCGUAAUGAAUGUGGACUUCACCAGGAUAUUGAAGAGGAUCACGGUGCCCAGGGGAGCUGACGAGCAGAGGAGAAGCGUCCCUUUCCAGAUGCUUCUGCUGCUGGAGAAGAUGCAGGACAGCCGGCAGAAAGCAGUGCGGCCCCUGGAGCUGGCCUACUGCCUGCAGAAGUGCAACGUGCCCUUGUUUGUCCAACAUGAUGCUGCCCAACUGUACCUCAAACUCUGGAACCUGAUUAAGGACCAGAUCACUGAUGUGCACUUGGUGGAGAGACUGCAGGCCCUGUAUACGAUCCGGGUGAAGGACUCCUUGAUUUGCGUUGACUGUGCCAUGGAGAGUAGCAGAAACAGCAGCAUGCUCACCCUCCCACUUUCUCUUUUUGAUGUGGACUCAAAGCCCCUGAAGACACUGGAGGACGCCCUGCACUGCUUCUUCCAGCCCAGGGAGUUAUCAAGCAAAAGCAAGUGCUUCUGUGAGAACUGUGGGAAGAAGACCCGUGGGAAACAGGUCUUGAAGCUGACCCAUUUGCCCCAGACCCUGACAAUCCACCUCAUGCGAUUCUCCAUCAGGAAUUCACAGACGAGAAAGAUCUGCCACUCCCUGUACUUCCCCCAGAGCUUGGAUUUCAGCCAGAUCCUUCCAAUGAAGCGAGAGUCUUGUGAUGCUGAGGAGCAGUCUGGAGGGCAGUAUGAGCUUUUUGCUGUGAUUGCGCACGUGGGAAUGGCAGACUCCGGUCAUUACUGUGUCUACAUCCGGAAUGCUGUGGAUGGAAAAUGGUUCUGCUUCAAUGACUCCAAUAUUUGCUUGGUGUCCUGGGAAGACAUCCAGUGUACCUACGGAAAUCCUAACUACCACUGGCAGGAAACUGCAUAUCUUCUGGUUUACAUGAAGAUGGAGUGCUAAUGGAAAUGCCCAAAACCUUCAGAGAUUGACACGCUGUCAUUUUCCAUUUCCGUUCCUGGAUCUACGGAGUCUUCUAAGAGAUUUUGCAAUGAGGAGAAGCAUUGUUUUCAAACUAUAUAACUGAGCCUUAUUUAUAAUUAGGGAUAUUAUCAAAAUAUGUAACCAUGAGGCCCCUCAGGUCCUGAUCAGUCAGAAUGGAUGCUUUCACCAGCAGACCCGGCCAUGUGGCUGCUCGGUCCUGGGUGCUCGCUGCUGUGCAAGACAUUAGCCCUUUAGUUAUGAGCCUGUGGGAACUUCAGGGGUUCCCAGUGGGGAGAGCAGUGGCAGUGGGAGGCAUCUGGGGGCCAAAGGUCAGUGGCAGGGGGUAUUUCAGUAUUAUACAACUGCUGUGACCAGACUUGUAUACUGGCUGAAUAUCAGUGCUGUUUGUAAUUUUUCACUUUGAGAACCAACAUUAAUUCCAUAUGAAUCAAGUGUUUUGUAACUGCUAUUCAUUUAUUCAGCAAAUAUUUAUUGAUCAUCUCUUCUCCAUAAGAUAGUGUGAUAAACACAGUCAUGAAUAAAGUUAUUUUCCACAAAA